AGAACUGUGGCGCUUUCUGGGUAAAGAUGGACGUCCACGAUCUCUUUCGCCGGCUCGGCGCGGGGGCCAAAUUCGACACGAGACGCUUCUCGGCAGACGCAGCUCGAUUCCAGAUAGGAAAAAGGAAAUAUGACUUUGAUUCUUCGGAGGUGCUUCAGGGACUGGACUUUUUUGGAAACAAGAAGUCUGUCCCAGGUGUGUGUGGAGCAUCACAAACACAUCAGAAGCCCCAAAAUGGAGAGAAAAAAGAAGAGAGCCUAACUGAAAGGAAGAGGGAGCAGAGCAAGAAAAAAAGGAAGACGAUGACUUCAGAGACAGGGUUUCACCAUGUUAGCCAGUAUGGUCUCGAUCUCCUGACCUCGUGAUUCACCCACCUUGGGCUCCCAAAGUGCUGGGAUUACAGAUGUGAGCCACCACGCCCAGCCAGAAAUUGCUUCCCAAGAAGAAGGUGCUACUAUACAGUGGAUGUCAUCUGUAGAAGCAAAGAUUGAAGACAAAAAAGUUCAGAGAGAAAGUAAACUAACUUCCGGAAAGUUGGAGAAUCUCAGAAAAGAAAAGAUAAACUUCUUGCGGAAUAAACACAAAAUUCACGUCCAAGGAACCGAUCUUCCUGACCCAAUUGCUACAUUUCAGCAACUUGACCAGGAAUAUAAAAUCAAUUCUCGACUACUUCAGAACAUUCUAGAUGCAGGUUUCCAAAUGCCUACGCCAAUCCAAAUGCAAGCCAUCCCAGUUAUGCUGCAUGGUCGGGAACUUCUGGCUUCUGCUCCAACUGGAUCUGGAAAAACAUUAGCUUUUAGCAUUCCUAUUUUAAUGCAGCUGAAACAACCCGCAAAUAAAGGCUUCAGAGCCCUGAUUAUAUCACCAACACGAGAACUUGCCAGCCAGAUUCACAGAGAGUUAAUAAAAAUUUCUGAGGGAACAGGAUUCAGAAUACACAUGAUCCACAAAGCAGCAGUGGCAGCCAAGAAAUUUGGACCUAAAUCAUCUAAAAAGUUUGAUAUUCUUGUGACUACUCCAAAUCGACUAAUCUAUUUAUUAAAGCAAGAUCCCCCCGGAAUCGACCUAGCAAGUGUUGAGUGGCUUGUAGUAGACGAAUCAGAUAAACUGUUUGAAGAUGGCAAAACUGGGUUCAGAGACCAGCUGGCUUCCAUUUUCCUGGCCUGCACAUCCCACAAGGUCCGAAGAGCUAUGUUCAGUGCAACUUUUGCAUAUGAUGUUGAACAGUGGUGCAAACUCAACCUGGACAAUGUCAUCAGUGUGUCCAUUGGAGCAAGGAAUUCUGCAGUAGAAACUGUAGAACAAGAGCUUCUCUUUGUUGGAUCUGAGACCGGAAAACUUCUGGCCGUGAGAGAACUUGUUAAAAAGGGUUUCAAUCCACCUGUUCUUGUUUUUGUUCAGUCCAUUGAAAGGGCUAAAGAACUUUUUCAUGAGCUCAUAUAUGAAGGUAUUAAUGUGGAUGUUAUUCAUGCAGAGAGAACACAACAACAGAGAGAUAACACAGUCCACAGUUUCAGAGCAGGAAAAAUCUGGGUUCUGAUUUGUACAGCCUUGCUAGCAAGAGGGAUUGAUUUUAAAGGUGUGAACUUGGUGAUCAACUAUGACUUUCCAACUAGCUCAGUGGAAUAUAUCCACAGGAUAGGUCGAACUGGAAGAGCAGGGAAUAAGGGAAAAGCAAUUACAUUUUUCACUGAGGAUGAUAAGCCAUUAUUAAGAAGCGUUGCUAAUGUUAUACAGCAGGCUGGGUGUCCUGUACCAGAAUACAUAAAAGGUUUUCAGAAACUACUAAGCAAACAAAAGAAAAAGAUGAUUAAGAAACCAUUGGAAAGGGAGAGCAUUAGUACAACUCCAAAAUGUUUCUUAGAAAAAGCUAAGGAUAAACAGAAAAAGGUCACUGGUCAGAACAGCAAGAAGAAAGUAGCUCUUGAAGACAAAAGUUAAAAACAGACUUUAAAAAUACUGUCCCAGAAAUGUAAUUUUAUGAUCCCAGCAUGAAUGUUAUUUUCAUGGAAUACUUGAAGUCUUACAGUCACCUGUACCAAACAUUUGAAAUCAACUACAAGUACAUGGGACUGGUGAUAAAUGAUCCUAAACUAUCAAGUCAGUUUCAAUUUGUAGGUGCCUUUUUUUUUUCCUGUAGAGAUGAGGGUCUUGCCAUGUUGUCCAGGCUGGUCUUGAACUCCUGACCUCACACAAUCCUCCUGCCUUAGCCUCCUGAGUAACUGAGAUUACAGGCACAAGCUGCUGCACCCAGCUCUGUAGGUGACUUUUAAAUGAUUAUACAAUGGAAAUAACAUUCAUUGACAUUUCUGUGGUUUGAAUCCAGAGAGAUACUUCUUAUAGAAAAACAAAUGUUUAUGCUAAAAAUAACACCAAAAUGUGGUGAACUCUUAAGGACUUUUCCCUUCAAGUGUGAAGGAAGGUGUGAUGAAUGCUGUGGAGAGGCAUCUGGAACAGAAAUUCAAAAUAAAGCCUUGACAUUAAAUACCCCUUCCACUGCUCACUUUGUGGAUGGUAGCAUGAGCUGUCUACCAAGAAGAAACCUGCUGCUCUCUUAAUUUUAAUAUUUCCUAAUUUGUUGAUGGCCUUUUGUGUUGUGAACCACAACAAAGAGAGGCCUCUUUUGUGGCUGGUUAUUCCAGUUCCCUGGGAUUUUAAAUUCUUUGGUCUAUUAAGUAUCCUUGUAUUGGAUACGUAAUACCUUAGUGCUGUCAUAAUGUUGUACAAGAUCAUGAUCAGCUUCUCCCUUUCUUCAUUUUCUGUGAUUUAACCAUGUUCUUUCCUGUCUCUUUCCAUUUAAGAUAUUUUAUUUGAAUACUGAUAAACAUUUUAUCCUGAUAAGGAAGAAUGUUCUUGUUACUUGAUAUACCUCUGUCUUCAUUCUCUUACAGCUUAUCUUUCCUUAGGUUGAUGGUGCCUCAUUUAAUAAGUAGAUCUCUACUUAAGCUAAAGGAUUAUGAUCAUAUGGUGUUGGAGACUAUUAGCUAUUAGAUUUUUCUCAAAAUAUGAGUUUUGUACAAUGGAAUGAAAAAGUGACUUCAUAUACGUAAGACUGGUGCCUAAGAAUGACUUGAAUGUUAUCAGUACUACCACAGAACUAUAAUAUACAUUGCCUUUUCUCAGCAGCAUUUGAAUUCAACUUAUUUAUUUCCUCUAUUUGUAGCUUUUUGUUCUAGAGUCAGAACAGGUGGACUUUGCUUUGAAUAUUUUAGAUGGGACAAAAAUUGUUCAUCUUCGGAAUUUAUUUAAAGAAAGAUCUACUGGUACAGGGUGUAAAAAUACUUACAAGAAUAUGAUUUUUUUGUUUGUUCAUGCAAACAGAUCCUUUACCCAAUAUAUAUUCUGGAGGUAGGUAUACUGGUGCAACCCAUUUGCCAGCUGUGUGACUUUGAGUAAGUUCUUAAUUUCUCAGAGUUUCAGUGUUCUCAUCUAUAAAAUUAUGUCUCCAAUUGUGAGUACCUAGCACUGUACCUGAUACAUAGUAAACUCACAAUAAAUAUUUCUUAAACAUAGAUUUUGUUAGGAAUACAGGCUUGAUAACACAGUCCUUACCCUUACAAUGUAAUGUUAGAGAUAAAGGAGCAAAUAGAGUCACGCAUCACUUAAUGACAGAGAUAUGUUCUGAGAAAUGCAUCGUUAGGUGAUAUUGUCAUUGUGUAAACAUCAUGUUGUUUACUUCCACAAACCUAGAUGGUAUAGCCUACCAGUACACCUAGGCUAUAUGGUAUAGUCUGUUGCUCCUAGGCUACAAACCCGUAUAGCAUGUUACUGUCCUGCAUGCUAUAGACAGUUGGAACAUGUAGACUUGUAUAAACACUGCACACUUAACCUAUACUAAAUUUAUUGAAAAUAUUUUUCUUGGCCAGGCGUAGUGGCUCAUGCCUGUAAUCCUAACACUUCGGGAGGCCUAGGCGGGCAGGUUGUCUGAGCUCAGGAGUUUAGAGACCAGCCCGGGCAACAUGGCAAAACCCCAUCUCUACUAAAAAAAAUACCAAAAAAAGUUAGCCGGGUGUGGUGGCAUAGUCCCGGCUACUCAGGAGUCUGAGGCAGGAGAAUAGCUUGAACCUGUGAGGCGGAGGUUGCAGUAAGCCGAGAUCGCGCUACUGCACUCCAGCCUGGGCGACAGGGCAAGACUGUCUUGAAAAUAAACACACACACACACAUUAUAUAUAUUAUGUAUUAUAUAUAUUAGAUAUAUAUUUUUUCUUCAAUAAAUUAACCUUAGCUUACUGUAACUUUUACUUUAUGAGUUUUUUUGUUUUGUUUUUUUUUUUUUUUUUGAGAAACAGGGUCUGUUACCUAAUUUGGAGUUUAGUGGCACAAUCAUGGCCCACUGCAGCCUUGACCUCUUAGACUCAAGUGAUCCUCAAACCUCAGCCUCCCGAGUAGCUGGUACUAUAGGUGCGGGCCACCAACACUCAGCUAAUUUUUAAAUUUUGUAGAGACGAGGUCUUGCUUGUUGUCCAGUUGGGUUUUUUAGAUUUUUUUUUUUUUUUUUUUUUGGAGAUGGAGUCUUGCUCUGUUGCCCAGGCUGGAGUGCAGUGGCAUGAUCUCGGCUCACUGCAACCUCUGACUCCUGGGUUCAAGUGAUUCUCCUGCCUCAGCCUCCCGAGUUGCUGGGACUACAGGCAUGCGCCACCACACCCAGCUAAUUUUUGUAUUUUUAGUGACAGGGUUUCACCAUGUUGGCCAGGCUGGUCUCAAACUCCUGACCUGGAGUGAGCCACUAUAUCCGGCCUUUAUAAACUUUUUUGAUUCUUGUCAUAACACUUAGCCUAAAAUGCAAAUGUACAGCUGUAGAAAAAUACUUUAUUUCUUUAUAUCCUUAUUCUAGAAGCUUUUUUUCUAUUAAUUUUUGUUUGUUUGUUUUGUUUUACUAUUUACUUCUAAAACUUUUUUGUUAAAAACCAUGGCACAAACACACACAUUAUGCUAGGCAUACAAAAGGUCAGGAUCAUCAGUCUCACUGUCUUCCACCCCCACUUCUCAUCCCACCAUUGUAUCUGCUGUCUGUGGCUGACCAAAACAUCAUCAUGUAGCACAUGACUAGUGUGGCAAGUGCUCUGUUAGAUGUAAGGCCAUGAUGCUAAAGCAUCACAAGAGGGCAUCUAACCCAGAUUGGGGAUGUCAUGGAAGGCCGACAUCCUGAGUUGAAUCCUGCAAAUGUAAAAACCAAUAGGCAAAGAAGAGGAACAAAAAGGAUUCCAGGACAAACUGAGGUCACAUCUAUGAUCCUUGACUUUAUUGUGUCUGUUUAAAGUAUCUACAGUAACCUGUAUCAACUUAGUCAGUGUAUUAAUACUAAAUUUAGCUCCUUCAAAGCAGUUGGAACUAUGUGCUACAUAAAUUUCAGCUUCACACAAGGAAGGGAAGGAGUGAAAUUAGUGAACAGGCAGUUACAGCAAAAGAAAAAACAUAAAAAUUGAAUAGCUGGCUCUGGUGAAAUGAGCAAGGACUUUAGAGUCAAACUGGCCUGGAUUUGAAUCCUGAUCCUCAUUGCUUGUAGCUGUAUGAUCUGGACAAAUGACAGUAACUGUUUCUAACCUUGAUUUUCUCAUCUGUAAGAUGCCAAUUGUAACUCCUAAGGAUACUGAGGAUUUUUUAAAAUGCGUGUACAGUUCCUGACCAGUGGUUUGUGCCUAAUAACUUAUUACAAAUUAUUACCCAGUAAAAACCUUGAGACAAGAGUGAAAACGUAAAGCUAAUUAAUCCAUUACUUGUUAGCAAGCAAACUACGUGCUUGAGAAAAUUACUCAACUUUCAUGUUUUACUUCCAGACAGUAGUUUGAUUAAAAGAAAAAAAAAAAUCACAGCCCAGGCAUGUGGCUCACACCCUGGCACUUGGAGGCCGAGGUGGGAGCAUAGCUUGAGCCUAGCAGUUUGAAACUAGCCUGGGCAACAUAGAUCCUAUCUCUACAAAAAAAAAAAAAAAAAAAAAAAAAAAAAUUGGCCCGGUGUGGUGGUGCAUGCCUGUGGUCCCAGCUACUCAGGAGGCUGAGGCGAGAGGAUCGCUUGAGCCAGGGAGGCUGAGGCUGCUGUGAGCCAUGAUCAUGCCACUGCACUCCAGCCUGGACAACAGAGCAAGACCCUGUCUCAAAAAAAAAAAAAAUCAGUAAAAAAUAUGCCGAAAUAGCUUCAGAGUAAUUAUGAAUUGCCUUCCAAAAACCACUGUUUUGCACUUGCCUGCAAGAAUAGGAAAAACAAAAGGACUGUAAGGUGGCAGGAUGGCAGAACCAAACAAGAGUAGUACACCUUGGAGUUUUUUCGAAAUAUGGGUUGGGUUUUUGGGCUCUUGGUUGAUUUAAAAUAAAAUUUAAAUGCCUUCAGCGUCUGUGAUAGGUGCCAACAUGAAGCUACCGAGUUCCAGAGAAAGAGGGGAGAGCUGAUCACUCAUCAGUGCUGCGAGACUAUCAAAGGGCCCUUCAGGACCUAUCUGUUCUUUGUGUGUAAAGAGUAACAAUAAAAGAACACCAGUGUACCCACCGUAUAGUUUAAAAA